GGUUCUGCGCCGGAUCCGGGAGAGGGGCGGGCGCCAUUGUGCUUCGCUGCCGACUGCAUUUCCUCAGUCACGGGCCUAGAACUCCAAGGAGAAAGGCGGCGGUGCGUGUUGCUGCGAGUGGGACGCGCACUGGUCGGUGCCGGCUCAGGAGCCGGGGUAAUGAGCUGCGGAGCUAGUUCUUCUCCGUCUUGGGCGCUAGUUCGGGACCAGGCCGCGAGUGGGGGAGGGGAGGAAACGAAGAGGCCUGGGGACGCGGAGGCCGCUUCCUCUCAGGAUGAGGAAUUCAUGAUUUGUUCCUGUAGCUGAAACAUACAUUGAAUGCUUUCUGCCCUGGCAUGAACUUACAUGGUCAGAGCUGGUUUUUCCUGCCCUCAAAUAUAUUUCUCUGACUCUACCGGUUAGACUAGAAAAAUCUUUAAGAAUGGAGUCUAAACCUUCAAGGAUUCCAAGAAGAAUUUCUGUUCAACCUUCCAGCUCCUUAAGUGCUAGGAUGAUGUCUGGAAGCAGAGGAAGUAGUUUAAAUGAUACCUAUCACUCAAGAGACUCUUCAUUUAGAUUGGAUUCUGAAUAUCAGUCUACAUCAGCAUCAGCAUCUGCGUCACCAUUUCAAUCUGCAUGGUAUAGUGAAUCUGAGAUAACUCAGGGAGCACGCUCAAGAUCGCAGAACCAGCAACGGGAUCAUGAUUCAAAAAGACCUAAACUUUCCUGUACAAACUGUACUACCUCAGCUGGGAGAAAUGUUGGAAAUGGUUUAAACACAUUAUCAGAUUCAUCUUGGAGGCAUAGUCAAGUUCCUAGAUCUUCAUCAAUGGUACUUGGAUCAUUUGGAACAGACUUAAUGAGAGAGAGGAGAGAUUUGGAGAGAAGAACAGAUUCCUCUAUUAGUAAUCUUAUGGAUUAUAGUCACCGAAGUGGUGAUUUCACAACUUCAUCAUAUGUUCAAGACAGAGUUCCUUCAUAUUCACAAGGAGCAAGACCAAAAGAAAACUCAAUGAGCACUUUACAGUUGAAUACAUCAUCCACAAACCACCAAUUGCCUUCUGAACAUCAGACCAUACUAAGUUCUAGGGACUCCAGAAAUUCUUUAAGAUCAAAUUUUUCUUCAAGAGAAUCAGAAUCUUCCCGAAGCAAUACGCAGCCUGGAUUUUCUUACAGUUCAAGUAGAGAUGAAGCCCCAAUCAUAAGCAAUUCAGAAAGGGUUGUUUCAUCUCAAAGACCAUUUCAAGAAUCUUCUGACAAUGAAGGUAGGCGGACAACGAGGAGAUUGCUGUCACGCAUAGCUUCUAGCAUGUCAUCUACUUUUUUUUCACGAAGAUCUAGUCAGGAUUCCUUGAAUACAAGAUCAUUGAAUUCUGAAAAUUCUUACGUUUCUCCAAGAAUCUUGACAGCUUCACAGUCCCGUAGUAAUGUACCAUCAGCUUCUGAAGUUCCCGAUAAUAGGGCAUCUGAAGCUUCUCAGGGAUUUCGAUUUCUUAGGCGAAGAUGGGGUUUGUCAUCUCUUAGCCACAAUCAUAGCUCUGAGUCAGAUUCAGAAAAUUUUAACCAAGAAUCUGAAGGUAGAAAUACAGGACCAUGGUUAUCUUCCUCACUUAGAAAUAGAUGCACACCUUUGUUCUCUAGAAGGAGGCGAGAGGGAAGAGAUGAAUCUUCAAGGAUACCUACCUCUGAUACAUCAUCUAGAUCUCAUAUUUUUAGAAGAGAAUCAAAUGAAGUGGUUCACCUUGAAGCACAGAAUGAUCCUCUUGGAGCUGCUGCCAACAGACCACAAGCAUCUGCAGCAUCAAGCAGUGCCACAACAGGUGGCUCUACAUCAGAUUCGGCUCAAGGUGGAAGAAAUACAGGAAUAUCAGGGAUUCUUCCUGGUUCCUUAUUCCGGUUUGCAGUCCCUCCAGCACUUGGGAGUAAUUUGACCGACAAUGUCAUGAUCACAGUAGAUAUUAUUCCUUCAGGUUGGAAUUCAGCUGAUGGUAAAAGUGAUAAAACUAAAAGUGCGCCUUCAAGAGAUCCAGAAAGAUUGCAGAAAAUAAAAGAGAGCCUCCUUUUAGAGGACUCAGAAGAAGAAGAAGGUGACUUAUGUAGAAUUUGUCAAAUGGCAGCUGCAUCAUCAUCUAAUUUGCUGAUAGAGCCAUGCAAGUGCACAGGAAGUUUGCAGUAUGUCCACCAAGACUGUAUGAAAAAGUGGUUACAGGCCAAAAUUAACUCUGGUUCUUCAUUAGAAGCUGUAACCACCUGUGAACUAUGUAAAGAGAAGUUGGAGCUUAACCUGGAGGAUUUUGAUAUUCAUGAACUACAUAGAGCUCAUGCAAAUGAACAAGCUGAGUAUGAGUUUAUCAGCUCUGGUCUCUACCUAGUGGUGUUAUUGCACUUGUGCGAACAAAGCUUUUCUGAUAUGAUGGGAAAUACAAAUGAACCAAGCACACGUGUCCGAUUUAUUAACCUUGCAAGAACUCUUCAGGCACAUAUGGAAGAUCUCGAAACUUCAGAGGAUGAUUCCGAAGAAGACGGAGACCAUAACAGGACAUUUGAUAUUGCCUAACUUCAUAUAAGACAGAUGGAUGAUCUGUGAACAUAAGUGUUUAUUAAAAAUGGCAAUUAAAUAUAAAUUACUUUUGUGGGGGAAUGCCUAAUAAAUACAUUGACUAUAUAUAAAAUGAAUAUAUACAUACACAUGUAUGCCUGUAUAUAUAUAUUCAUUCUCCAGUGUUGCUGAAUUAAAAUUCUGCUGGACUUUUUAACAUAGCAAAUCCGAUGUUUAUAAACUGGUAAUCAAAAAGGUUUUUUCUUUUAGGUGAGUGGGAAAGUAUUACCCUUGUUUUAAAUAUCUAAGCAAUGCCUAUCAACCCUUUUUUGUGUUAUGAUUACUGUAGUCAUAUUUAUGAAAAAAGGUUUGUGUUUUACUCUUGCUAGUGAGAAAAGUGGGACAAAAUAUACUUUUGAAAUAAAAUGCUAUAUGGCACCUAAUUAUUUUUUCUUUUAAAAUGCCUUAAGUUGCAGUCUCAUUUUGAUAAUCAUUUGCUUCCAGUGUUUAAAAAUUAAAAAAAGAAUGGGGAGAAGGUUAUGAGAAGAGCAUUAUUAAGUUUCCAAAUUUAAUUUGAAUUCCAAAUUCACCUAGCAAUAAAAUCUAAUUUUUAAAAAGUAUAUAAAUAUAAAAUGUAUAAAUGAUGGAUAGAUUUUUGUAUUGAUUUGCAAAAUGCAGAUUAUAUUUGAUAGGCUAUAGUAUGUAGAUAUUCCUUUUAGGAAUAUUACAGCUGUAAAUUAUAUGAGACUUGCCAGUCAAAUGCUAUUUGGUUUAAAAAAAUUAUUGCAAUCUCAAGUUAAUGGAAUAUUUUUAAAUCCCACAUUCAGAGUUUAAAACACUGGUUUUCAAUGUGUUUUUUAGUGUUGUCACUUGUUUAUAGAUAAAUAUAUAAAUAACCUGUUUGGAUCCUGGUCCUUUUUAACUGUUCCUUGGUAAUUCUGAGCAUUUAUUUGAUGACUUAAUAUUUUUCACUACCUUUGGAGAACAGAUGAACAUUAUUCACCAUGAAUGGAUCUAUACUGUGUGGUCAUGAGUUGUGUAUACUUCCAUAACACUGUAUUUUUCUUCUGUCAGUACCCUUAGGAUACACUUUAAAACACCUUAAGGUCUGAUGUUAUGGCAACAAACUACUUUUUCAAACCUAAAUAGGAACCAUGUAAUUUCUCAAAAGUGAUUGAACAGUUUGCCCACACUUAGUUUGUUGGUCUUAUGUAAAACAUUGGCUCAAAAUAAAGUACACACUGAUUUAUUUUACUGUUUGAAAUGUUUCCUUUUAAACUGGUGCUCAAAGAAGACAUCAGACUUCAUAACCAAGAAUUUUAUUACAAUUUCAAAUCUCAUUUUAAGCAAUAAUAUAAAUGUUCUAAAACAUUUGCUCACCUCUUGCCAGUUACCUUUGCAUUGUCUGUCUUAAAGCAAAAAUAUAAAAUUUAAGGGUGGUAGUUUUAAUAUAUUCUGUGGGUCCUAAGGGAUGCUUUGAAUUUGAAGUAUAUAUACUUUUAAUAAAAUUCAGUAUGACAGUUGUCUUCUGCUUAACCCAUAAAACUUUAUUUAAAAAAUUUAACUAGAUGGUACAAAACAUUCAUUGGUAUGCACAUAAUUCUGUAUAGUUUUGUUAUUAAAUGCUAAAUGACAGUGAUAACAAUGGCUUAAGCUUUACAGUAUUCUUGUAGUUCCCUAGUACCACUUAGUAUUUAAAUAUUGUCAUAUUAGCUUCAGAUUAUCAUGUAAAUGACGGUAGAGGAAUAAGAGAAAAGGCUUUCAUUGGUUAUCAGUUUUAAAUUCUGAACAAAAGAGACCAUACACUGCUCACUACAAGAAUGCAAUUUUCUAAGAAAAUGUAGUUUAAAAUGUUAUUCUGAAUAUCUGCCAAAGAAUUAUAUUGUUAUUACUAGCUAGAACCAAGAUGUUGAAGAAAGCAGUUUCUACAUUCUGGAUGUAGUAAACAAGCCUGCCUGUGUAAUCCAAUUAUCUCUUCACUAAUGAGUAGAUAAGGUGCCUGUUAUAGAUGUUCUGGUAUAUAAAGAAAAAAUGUAGGCCAAGUGUGGUGGCUCACGCAUGUAAUCCCAGCACUUUGGGAGACCAAGGUGGGUGGAUCACUUGAGGUCAGGAGUUUGAGACCAGCCCAGUCAAUAUGGCGAAACCCCGUCUCUACCAAAAAUACAAAAAGUUAGCUGGGUGUGGUGACAGAUGUCUGUGGUCCCAGCUACUAAGGAGGCUGAGGCAGGAGAAUUGCUUGAAAACCUGCAAGGCGGAGAUUGGAGAGAGCCAAGAUCGAGCCACUGCACUGUAGCCUGGGCAGCACAGUGAGACUCCAUCAUAUAUAUAUAUAUAGCACUUCAUUACCAGAGGCCUCUUGGCCUGUUGAAAAAUGAAACCAAAUAUUGAAAAUUAAAUCAGAGUUUAAAGCAGCUAUUUUGGAAGAGCUGCCAUUAGGUAGAAAGUAUCAAAAUGUACAAAAGAAAGUUGUAUGGGAGUUGAGUGGAAGGUAGGAUUUAAGAGCAGCACUGCCCAAUAAAACUUCCUAUAAUGAAAAUGUUCUAUAAUGUAUGUUGCCCAGUACAGUAGCCACUAACCACCUGUGAUUUGAACACUUGACAAUGUGGCUAAUGUAAUUCGAAAACUGGAUUUUAAACUAAAUUUACUUAAAUAGCCUCAUGUGGCUAGUGGCUCAUUGGACAUUGUAGUUGUAGACGUUUGAGACUGUUGGUUUUAAGUUGGACUUAAUCACUUUCCUACCCAAAUUCUACCACUCCUUUAAGAACUCCUUUAGAACUCUUUUAGUUCACAUAAUACGCCAUAUUUUUUUUACUGUGCCUGUAGUUCUUCAAGGAGUGGUACAAUUUGGGUAGGAAAACCAGGCAGGAAUUCCAGGGUAGUGUUCAAUAUUGACAUUAGUAAUAGUCUAUCAAUAAUAAAAUAGACAUCUCAAUCACUAUACAAAAUCUCAGAAAUGUAAAGCUCUUACAGAGCAUGCUUGUGCUUGUGUAACAGCUGGUGUAAUGCCUGCAUUUUCAGUACCAUGUAGCCGCACUGUUAAUAGUUUUCUAUCACUUUUUAGUUACUCAUGUCUCAUUAAUGAUAGUGCCAUUAAUUGUGAUGAGUGUUUUCGAUUCAUGUGGUCAAUAAAAAGAGACUACACAAGCUGGAACUUUGUUGCCAUUAGUCAAGCUAGUGAGAUAGUAUAUCUAUCUAUCUCCCCAGAAGAAAGUAAGAUAAUUGAUGGGGUGUGGAUUCAGAAGAGGGAUUACUUUUCUUUGAGCCUCAGACUUCUAGACAGUAUACUUCAGUCAGUAAUGGACCACAUAUAGAACAGUGUUUCCUUAGUAGACCAUAUUUUUACUGUACCUUUUCUAUAUUUAGAUACACAAAUAUUGUGUUACAAUUGUCUGCAGUAUUCAGCACAGUAACAUGCUGUGUAGGUUUGGGACAAAAUAGGCUCUACCAUCUGGGUUUGUGUAAAUACAAGCUGAUUUUCACACAAGAUUCCCUAACUAUGCAUUUCUUAGAACGUAUCCCCAUUGAUAAGUGAUACGUGACUAAUUUACGUGAAAUUUAUACAUUCUUUAUCUUUCCUGUUUUUGGUUUAUUGAUGGUGAGGAAAAUUACUCGUUUCAGCUUUUUCAUUUUUUUACUCCCCAAAUGAUUUUCACCUUUUUCUUAAAAUGUACAAUAAAUGCACUGAAAACUUUGAUCACUGUCA